AAAGACCUUGCUGUUCUAUCCUUUGAGUUACUGUUGGGACAACUGGGAAGAGGGAAGAGUUGCGAUAAAGAACAAGGAAGGCUCCAUGACUGGAAGUUUAGUCCGCCCAGUUUUUGUACUGGAAGGGCUUAUUGCUGAUUUCAUUAAGAAAACGUACGAAUGGGGGCUUCUGUCACCUCAGAAUAUCUUAUACUGUACUCACGUAUUUUGGGGUCUCAGUUGACCAUGGGUUACAAACUAUGGCUAGGGGGGCAGGGAUCCACUGUAUUGUAAGCUAUAUAUUUUUUCCAUUUAGAAACAUAGGCUUUCAAGGGGACUUAAUCUUUUUGUAACCCUCAAAGCCACCUUAGGAAGGAAGGUAACAGUUUGCUGUUGAGAGAAAGGUUAAGGAACUGUGGCUGUGAAGGCACAUACCCAGCUGCUACCUGUGAGCCCUCCACUCUUUCCCUGCCCUCUGCAGGCACGCUGGGGUUGAGGCCUCUGAGCCUGGGCCACAAAUCACAUGCACACAUGUGUAAGUGCAUGUUCCCCCACAGCACUGUGCUGGGGGAAGCAGGCACAGAUAGGGGAAGAUACUUAACCGAGCUGCCACGCAGGGAUAGGAUAUUUAAAACACAAGCACCCUGAACUCCCAGUCCAGUGUUCUUUCCACUCAUCUGCCAGAUUCUGAGAGCUUCCUGCCUGGUUUUGGAACUACUUGAAGUACAAAGAGGAAACUAAUGGAGGGUGGGCAAAGGCCUUCCACUUGGUUUGUCUGGGAGUACCCUCAAGUCUACAGCCUACCCCGCUGAUGGAAGCAGGCCAGCACUGGCCUGUCUCUUGGGGAGAACAAAUGUGGAUAGGCAGUGGGAAAAAGACCAGUUGGGCCAGAGUAGUUGCAGAAGGGGACAUGGGUUGGCCUGAGUCAGGUUGGGACAUAGAAAUCUCUAAAUAAUUGGUUUGUCCAACAAUCCUGCACCCCUAGUGUGGGCACAAGUGCCUCACACUAGGCCACUUUGUGACAAGAACGUCAUGCAGGUUUGAGAUUUGUAGAAGCCUGGCUUCAUUUUUUUUUUUUUUUGUUUCUCCACACCUAAACCGGUGCCUCAGUUUUUCAGCCUGUAAAAUUGGGCUGCUUCUUAGAUAUGCCAUUGGCUUGCUGCUGGCCUCCUCCGUCCCUUUGGAGGAGGGCUGAGGAUGAGCAGCUGACUUGGGUUAGCCCUCAGAUGAAAGGGACCAGAGUACUGAUGAUUGGGGGUUUAAAGACUGGAUGGAGUUUAAAUACUGGAUGGAUCCAGGGAAGCCAGCCUUUCUCUGCAUCACUGCAUCCCUGCCCCAUGCUUGUUUGCACUGCAGGGAGUAGCAGCUAUGGCACCCAGCAGCCCUGUGCCAAGUCUCCAGGCUGGGGAGGGUCUGCUCCAGGGAGUGAGGGGGUGCCUUGGUUUGCACUCUGGGAGCCAAAUUCCCUCGAGGUAGGAUAUUGCUCAAGAUGGCAUUUGCCAGAGCUGAGGAGUCUAAGGCACCAUCUUUUCAUUUCUCCUGGGGUCUAGUCUUAUUACUCAAACCCUUGGAUAUAACGGGUUGGUACUACCUUUGGGAAGACUUAAUCUCUUGCAUUUCCUCUGAGGUGGGAUUGGAGAGGCAGUAAAGGUCCCUAUUGGCUGUUGCUGGGCUUGUAGUUGCUCUGGGAUGUUCUCUGCUGUCCCUGCCCCAGGCCUUUUCUGCCCACAUAUCAUCACUGCCAUUGCCCCUCUGAGGUGCCAGCUCUUUGGAGAUCCUAGACUUGAAGCAGGUCAGAAUCUAAAAGGGCUUUGGUCACUAAGAAGCCGUCUGGUCACUUCUUUUACAGAAAACCAAGUCUGUAUUUUGACCAAAGUCUCUCAGGUGGCACCAGGGGGGAUCACAGUGCCUGCAUUAGGAUUUGUAGGCUUUGUUUCCUUGAGGAAAGAAACAGUUGAAACUCAGUAAUUUCAGGGAAAAAAAGAAAAACAGGAGGCCCUUUGAAUGGUCGGUGCUGCCAGGGGGAGAUCAGAAGAGGACUAGGGCUGGAUAUAGUGGCUCACACCUGUAAUCCCAGCGCUUUGGGAAGCCAGGGCAAGAGGAUCACUUGAGCCUAGGAGUUUCAGUCUAGCUUGGACAAGAUGGCAAGACUGUCUCUACAAAAAUUAAAAUUAGCUGGGUGUCCCAGCUAAUUUAGUCACAGCUACUUGGGUGGCUGAUCCAGGAAGAUCGUGUGAGUUCAGGAGCUUGAGGCUGCGGUGAGCUAGGAUUGUGCCACUGCACUCCAGCCUGGGUAACAGAGUGAGACCUCGUAUCUAAAAAACGUAAGUGAAUAAAAACAAGAACUUCAAAUACAAAAAUUAGUUGGGUGUGGUGGCAAGCACCUAUAGUCCCAGCUACUCAGGGGACUAAGGUGGGAGGAUCACCUGAACCCGGGGAGGUCGAAGCUGCAGUGAACUGUGAUCAUGCCACUGCAUUCCAGUCUGGGUAACAAAGUGAGACCCUCCCUCAAAAAAAAAAAAAAAAGGCGACUCCCCUGCGGCUUUGGUGCUUGCUGGAGCCCAGGCCUUCAGGUUGCAGAUGGUUCUAGAGCAUUGCCUUUGCAAUAAACAGUGUUUUUGAUUCUUGACUGUUUUUACUCACAUCAUUCCCUUUUCUGAGUUGCAUUAUCCCCACCUGGCAGGUGAACUAACGGGCUCAAGAGGAGUGGAUUCUGGUGGCCUCAGUCCCCUGUAGGGCCUACAGGCUUGAUCUGGAGCCUUUUGGGGACAAGAACCUAAUGUUUGUUUCCUGCAGUGCUGAGAGGGGUUUGGGGUAGCCUGGGAUUUCAUAUCCUUGGAGUCAGAUACCUUCUCACUGGAUAACCUUCGGCUAACCACUUAGCUGCCUUGAGUCUUCUAAAACUGGGAUAAUAGUCCCUCCAUUGUGAGGACUAAAAAACUUAAAUGCACAAAAGGGGCACGGCAGGAGGCCUGGCUUCCUGAGGUAAAUGCCUAGUAAGUGGUGGCCAUUAUUACUAUUAUUAGUAUUUUAAAGUAAAUAUGGCCGGGCUUGGUGGCUUAACUCCUGUAACCCCAGCACUUUGGGAGGUUAAGGUGAGAGUAUCCCUUGAGCCCAGGAAUUCAAGACCAGCCUAGGCGGCAUAGCAAGACCCAGUAUCUAUUUUAUUUUAUUUUGUAUAGAGACAGAGCAUUGGGUGAGCAAACAGUAAGAUUUUUAGGGUAAGAGAAGCUGUUCGGCUGUGAGGCAAAAGCAGGUGGACAAUUCCCUUCAGAACCUUCAUUCUUCUGGCAAAGCCAAGUUUUGGAGCUUGUUACAAAACUUAAACCCCAGCCCAGACUGAUCCCUUGUGACCUCAUAUCUGUCAGGACACUCAUCAUGUGGCUUCUUGGAUCACUGUUGGUUCCUGGUGCUGGAGAUUAGACUGGUGGGUAAAGGGAGAGUACCUCCUGCACCUCUCUUCUGGCUGCUGUUUGUGUGUGUAAUUGAAACUACCUGCUCUUGUAAACCAAUUAAGUCCUGUCUAUACAAGUGAGACCCUGCACUGGGGUUUGGAGACCUGGGUUCCUUCCUGGCAGUCUCACUCAUUGGCAGCUCAGUUCUUAAACAUUAAUCUGCCAUGAGCAAUUGCACAGGAAGCAUACAACUGCAGGUGUUCAAUUUAUGCCCACCUUCUUAAAUUAAUUUCUGGAGUUUAUAGAGGGAGUCAAGAAUCUGCAUUUCUCCCAAGCCAGCCCCUCUUCCCAGAUGCUCUGUAGACCACAGAAGUGGUAUUGCAAGCCUGCUAGCUCACUGAUCUACAGUUUCUACAAAUGUGAAGUGAGUGUUUUUCAAACUACCUUCUGCUCAGGAACUCCUGCUGAAUGGGAGUCACUCAGUUUAGUAACAUUUCUUUUGGAACAGCUCUGCUAUUUUUCUUUUCAAGUAAUUUAAGUGUUUAAUACAUACUAAGGAAUAUAAAUCUAAAAUAAAUAUCAAAACAACCCAAGUACAGUCUCGUGUCACUUAACAGGGAUACAUUCCGAGAAAUGUGUCAUUAGUUGAUUUUGUCAUCGUAUGAACCUAGAGUGUACGUACACAAACAAAUGGCACAACGUACUAUGGACUUAGGUUGUAUAGUAUAGCCUGUUGCUCCUGGGCUACAAACCUGUGUAGCAUGUUCCUAUACUGAAUACUGUAGGAGUUGUAAUACAAUGGUAAGUAUUUGUGUAUCUAAACAUAGAAAAAGUAUUGUAGGUCGGCCGCGGUGGCUCAUGCCUGUAAUCCCAGCACUUCCCAGCACUUUGGGAGGUUGAGGCGGGUAGAUCGCCUGAGGUCAGGAGUUCAAGAGCAGCCUGGCCAACGUGGUGAAACCCCAUCUCUGCUAAAAAAAAAAAAAAAUGCAAAAAUUAGCUGGGCAUGGUGACGGACACCUGUAAUCCCAGCUACUGGGGAGGCUGAGGUGGGAGAAUCAACUGAAUCCAGGAGACAGAGGUUGCAGUGAGCAGAGAUCACGCCACUGCACUCCAGCCUGGGUGACAGAGCGAGACUCUGUAUCAAAAAGAAAAAGUACUGUAAAAAUAUGGUAUAAAAUAUGGAAUAAAAAGUGUUCCUUCUUCAUACCCCCUGCUUCACUUUACUAGCCUUAAAAUAUUUUUAAAGAUUUUUUAAAAUGGCACACUGACUAUAGUCAGCAAUAAUUUAUUGUACAUUUAAAAAUAACAAAGUGUAACUGAAUUGUUUGUAACACAAAGAAAGGAUAAAUGCUGGAGAUGAUGGAUACCCCAUUUACCCUGAUGUGAUUAUUAUACCGUAUCAAAGUAUCUCAACUACCCCAUAAAUAUGUAAACCUACUAUGUACCUACACAAAUUAAAAAUUAAAAAAAUAUAUAUAAUAAAGUGGCACACUGGUAUAGGGCAGCUCUAUUAUAAUCUUACGGGACCAACUGUCAUAUUUGUGGAUGGAGAUGUCAUUAUUUGGCUCAUGACUAUACUUACUGCUGGUUUAAGAAGUGCAGGAUGGGUGCGGUGACUCACGCCUGUAAUCCCAGCACUUUGGGAGGCCGAGGCAGGCGGAUCACAAGUUCAGGAGAUCGAGACCAUCCUGGCUAACACGGUGAAACCCCGUCUCUAUUAAAAAUACAAAAAUUAGCUGGGCGUGGUGGUGGGCGCCUGUAGUCCCAGCUACUCGGGAGGCUGAGGCAGGAGAAUGGCGUGAACCCAGGAGUUAGAGCUUGCAGUGAGCCGAGAUCGCGCUGCUGCACUCUAGCCUGGGCCACAGAGCGAGACUCCGUCUAAAAAAAAAAAAAAAAAAAGUGCAGCUCUGAUUUAAAAAUAUUAAAUAUGGUAUUGUGGUUUUGGGUACCCCUGUCAGUUUAACAGUUGAAACUCAUUAGGUUACAUCAAAAUAACUGUUAAGUAUGUACAGAGAAAACCUACCUUAGAAUUACCUAGCAGAUUCCUGACUCCACCAUUGCUGAGCAAAAAAUCUCUGAAGGAUGGGACCCAGGAAUCUACGUUUUGACAAGCUCCUCACAUGAUAAUUCGAAUGCAUGCCAAAAAUCUUAAUAGCUUAUCCUGGAAAGCCGGCUGCAUUUAUGGAGAUCAAUGGGUAUAAGGACAAAAUCACAAGAUGUUAGAACUGGAAGGACUGUGGAUGAUAGGAUUCUGCCCACCCCUACCACAGGCCUCUGAAUAGAGAGACUGAAGACACUGGAGGGUAGUUCUUGCCAAGCAUCCAUAGCAAGAGCUCUGGUGUCUGCGCCAGGACUGUCAACCAGUCUCUUGACUUCUAGCCCAGGGCUCUGGUCACUCUUCCACUUUCAGUUUGGAACAUGGGGCAAUAGUCUUUCCUAACUAUGGUGUCCAGUUCUAACAAACUAAAAAUACAGGGGACACCCAGUUAAAUUUGAAUUUUAGAUAAAUCAAAUAUUUAGUAUAAGUAUGUCCCAGUAUUGCAUGGGACAUAUUUAGUCUAUAAAAUUACUGUUUAUCUGAAAUUUAGAUUUAACAGAGUGUCCUGAAUUGCUAUUUGCUAAAUCUGGCAACCAUAUUCUCUCCCCGCUUACCCCACCUUUUUUUGGGCACCAGUCAGGUUCAAGAAUUGCCCCAAAGAAAUGAAAAAUAAUUACCAUGCAUUUAUGGUACUAUUACUUCAUUUAAUCUGUUAAUCCUGUGAGCUAGCUGUCAUGGACCCCAUUAAUAGUUCAGGAAAGUGAGAGGUUAAGUCUGACUCCUGGGAUCAUCUCGGUAAGCUGUCAUUUUGCCUCCUCAUGAACCUAGUUGCUUGGCUCUCAUUGAUGUGUGGCCCAGUUAAUGCCUAUCAAGUUACAAGCUACAUGAGAGAUUGCUCAGUUUUGACUCAUCUGCCCCUGGCCUUGUGAGUUACUUAAUUGAUGAUGGCUCUUGGUUAGUACAUCCAAGAAUGGACUCCAAAGUCCACGCUGUUAACUGCUGCUCUAACCUGUCUCUUAACUCCGUGGCAUAGUAAAUUGUUGGUAGGGUGGCUUUGGGGUAGGGGUCGGACCCCCUCUACAUUCUCUCUUUUUUUUUUUUUUUUUUUUGAGAUAGAGUUUUGCUGUUGUUGCCCAGACUGGAGUGCAGUGGCGCAAUCUCGGCUCACCGCAACCUCCACCUCCCGGAUUCAAGCGAUUCUCCUGCCUAAGCCUCCCGAGUAACUGGGAUUACAGGCAUGCGCCACCACACCUGGCUAAUUUUGUAUUUUUAGUAGAGACGGGGUUUCUCCAUGUUGGUCAGUCUGGUCUCGGACUCCUGACCUCAGGUGAUCCGCCUGCCUCGGCCUCCCAAAGUGCUGAGAUUACAGGCAUGAGCCACUGUGCCCAGCCCCCCUCUACAUUCUCUAAAGGGGUGUGCUGGUGCCUUGAGAGCAUCCGUGUGCAGGGGUGGGGAGUCUGCAGGUGGGGCAGCACCCUGGCUGCUGAGCCUGUCCUGUCUCCAUGUUCAUAGCAUCCCAGGGCUUAACUCUUUCCCAGUUGGGUUGUAGCAUAUGACACUGAAGGAGCCUGUAGGCCAUCCUGAACUCACCGAGAGAGGCAAAUUAGCAGCUCCUGGGAAGCAAGGCUGCCUGGCCAGGCUGGCCUGGAUUGGGGGAACUAGUUGCUACUCGAGAACUCCAGCUUCCUAUCUGCUUUUGGGAUGACCCUCCCUGGAAAGUCCCUCCCACUGCUGUGGAAUUUUCAGGCUACCAAAUGUGCCCAGCCUGCCUCUCAGGACAGACAGACAGUGAGAAAAAGAUCUCCAGGGCCCACUAAGUCUUCCAGAGGGAGCUGAGACAUUCAGCCUUCCCUGGCAGGGCUCAAAGAGGAAAAAAGGGAUUGGAAAUGGGGCCCCUCUCAGAGCCACUUCAAAGCACCCUCCCCUGUGGUCAUGUGUUUCAGUUCCAUGUGAGUAGUUUUUCUUGACAGUAUCGGUAAUUUUGGGGAACAGUUCCUGUGACACUUUGGGUCCCUAAGGCCCUGCCCUGACCCUGUGAGUGGAUAUAGUUGGGCACAGAGUGUAUUUUGUUGAGGAGCAGAUAUUGGCUUCCUGGUUUGCCAAAGAGCUCUAGAUUGGGAGACAAGAACUUGAUGUUCCAGUGCCAGCUCUACAGCAAAUCACUGGUGACUUUGGCCUCUCCUGGUCCUCAGUUUUUCUGUAUGUACAAUGAGAUUCUCAAGUCUUUCCAGCCCUGACUUGGUCUGGGAUCACCCUCUCCACUCCAAUAAUGGGAAUAAUCCAAAGUAAUUUUUUGGGGAUUCAGAAGCCUCUUCCAACAAAGGAUGCCCUAAGAUUGGAAGGACAAUAAAAAUGAGUUUGUGGGCCGGCCACGGUGGCCCAUACCUGUAAUCCCAGUACCUUGGGAGGCUGAGGCGGGUGGAUCACUUGAGGUCAGGAGUUCAAGACCAGCCUGGCCAACAUGGUGAAACCCCAUCUCUACUGAAAAUACAAAAAAUUAGACAGGCUUGGUGGCUCGCGCCUGUAGUCCCAGCUACUCGGGAGGCUGAGGCAGGAGAAUUGCUUGAACUUGGGAGGUGGAGGUGGCAGUGAGCCUAGAUUGUGCCACACCCACUGCACUCCAGCCUAGGUGACAGAGUGAGACUCCGUCUCAAAAAAUAAAAAAAUGAGUUUGUGUUACCUGAGGUGGUGGCUGACCACCAAGGACAGGAAGAAAACCUCUGAGCUUGGCAGCCUCCCACAUCAGGGUAAUGGAGUCAGGUGUGCGUGUAGUUGUGUGUGCCUAGCAACCUGUCUGAGACGAUUGGCUUCUGAAGUCCAGGGCCUAGGAAAGCCCAAGGGAGCCCCGCAAGCUGAUUGUGCAUAGCUCAUUUGUUUAACUGGGAAUCAUCAUCAUACCUACCUUCUGGGCUCACGCCUGUAAUCCCAGCACUUUGGGAGGCCGAGGCGGGCGGAUCACGAGUCAGGAGAUCGAGACCAUCCUGGCUAAUAUGGUGAAACCCUGUCUCUACUAAAAAUACAAAAAAAUUAGCUGGGCAUGGUGACACACACCUGUAAUCCCAGCUACUCGGGAGGCUGAGGCAGGAGAAUGGCGUGAUCCUGGGAGGCGGAGCUUGCAGUGAGCCGAGAUGGCGCCAUUGCACUCCAGCCUGGGUGACAAGAGUGAGACUCCGUCUCAAAAAAAAGGAAAAAAAAAACGGAAAAAUAAAUGAGCUACUACAUGUAAAAAACUUUGGCAUCAUGCAAAGACAUUGUAAGGCAAGCUUGUCCAAAGGACGGCUUUGAAUGCGUCCUGACACAAAUUUGUACUUUCUUAAAACAUUGAGAUUUUCUUGCAAUUUUUGUUUUUUAGGUUCAUCAGCUAUCAUUAGUGUUAGUGUGUUUUACGUGUGGCCCAAGACAUUAAUUCUUCCAUUGUGGCUCAGGGAAGGCAAAAGAUUGGACACCUCUGUAGUAAGCUCUCAGUAAUUGAUUGCAGUCUAGUGGAGUUGAGAUACACACAGAUGCAACCAUUUCAGGCGGUAGUGAGUACCCUGAAGAUCUUAAAUUGUAGACUGAGUUAGAACUUGAUCCAGAGUUGCUGGUUUUGUGGCACUUUACAUUGGGCAGUCAGGAAGCCUCCUGAGGAGAAUUUAUAUUGAGAUCUAUGACUAGAUCUGAGGAGUCAGUCAUCUUGCUCUUCAACAUUGUGACCUUGGGCGAGUCCCUUCCUUCAGUUUCAUUUUCUGGACAACUGGAAUAAUUGUGUCUUUUUGAGAUAAUUAAGUAAAAUCAUACACAGCAACUUAGGUCAGUUUUUGGUACCUAGUCUUUAUGCAGUAAAAGGUGAUUAUUAUUACUGUUCUAACUAGAACCAAAUGUGCUCUUUAGAAAAGGCUGGGUUAGGGAGCUGGCACUUGGAGGCCAGGAGCUUUAGUGGCCGCUGAUAUAUUUCAGCUGUGUUGAUUAUUGAUCAGCUUUGAAGCAAGAUUUCAGGGACUGGUACCAGCAGUGGGAGUGGCCACAGCCACCCGAGGGUGGCUGGGUCCACAUCUGGGCGGGGAGAGUGGGAGCACUGGGCCACCUGGGUCACCACAGGCUAAAGAUAGUCAGCUGGGGCUGGGCCUGGGCUGGGCCAGGCUGGCCAGCAUCAUGUGACUGGAGCCUGGCCCACCCUUGCUCCUCCUCCCGGGCCAAGGGGAUGCAGACUCUGCAUUCCUGAGCUGACUGGUGGUCUGCAGCUUCCUUUCAGUGGGAACUCAAGAUGAUCUGACCUGAACAUUUCUCUCCUUCCCUUUCUCUGCCCACUCCUCUCCCUAAGAAUGCCCUUCCAGCCCCUCCUGCAUUUCAUCCGCAGGUCUAGGGAAAUUUGGGUGGGAGGACUGGGCAGAGAGGCCUCUGAGAGAUGGUACCGACAGCAGCAGCUGGUGACCAAGAACACUCUGCUCCAGCCAAGGUGGUGAGGGCAGCUGUUCCUAAACAGCGCAAAGGCAGCAAGGUUGGUGACUUUGGAGAUGCAAUCAAUUGGCCCACACCUGGAGAGAUAGCCCACAAGAGUGUUCAGCCACAGUCCCACAAGCCUCAGCCUACCCGUAAACUGCCACCCAAGAAGGACAUGAAGGAACAGGAGAAAGGAGAAGGGAGUGAUAGUAAGGAGAGUCCAAAAACCAAAUCAGAUGAAUCAGGGGAGGAAAAGAAUGGAGAUGAGGAUUGCCAGCGAGGCGGGCAGAAGAAGAAAGGAAACAAACACAAGUGGGUUCCAUUACAAAUAGACAUGAAGCCUGAAGUGCCCAGAGAGAAACUGGCUUCACGCCCCACUCGCCCACCGGAGCCUAGACACAUACCUGCCAAUCGCGGAGAGAUCAAAGGGUCUGAGUCUGCCACCUACGUGCCCGUGGCCCCCCCCACCCCAGCCUGGCAACCAGAGAUCAAACCGGAGCCUGCCUGGCACGACCAGGAUGAGACAUCGAGUGUGAAGAGUGAUGGGGCUGGUGGGGCGCGGGCUUCCUUCCGUGGCCGUGGACGGGGGCGUGGUCGCGGCCGGGGACGCGGCCGGGGUGGCACUCGAACCCAUUUUGACUACCAGUUUGGCUACCGAAAGUUUGAUGGUGUGGAGGGGCCUCGUACGCCCAAGUACAUGAACAACAUCACCUACUACUUUGACAAUGUCAGCAGCACCGAGCUUUACAGUGUGGAUCAGGAACUGCUCAAAGACUACAUCAAGCGCCAGAUUGAAUACUACUUCAGCGUGGACAAUUUAGAGCGAGACUUCUUCCUGCGAAGGAAAAUGGAUGCUGAUGGUUUCCUACCCAUCACCCUUAUUGCUUCCUUCCACCGAGUGCAGGCCCUUACCACUGACAUUUCACUCAUCUUUGCGGCCCUAAAGGACAGCAAGGUGGUGGAGAUCGUUGAUGAGAAAGUUCGUAGGAGGGAGGAACCAGAAAAGUGGCCUCUUCCCCCAAUAGUGGAUUAUUCACAGACUGAUUUCUCCCAGCUUCUCAACUGCCCUGAAUUUGUUCCCCGUCAGCACUACCAAAAGGAGACAGAGUCGGCACCUGGCUCUCCUCGUGCAGUCACCCCAGUGCCAACCAAAACAGAGGAGGUCAGCAACCUAAAGACACUACCCAAGGGCCUGUCUGCCAGCCUGCCUGACCUGGAUUCUGAGAACUGGAUUGAAGUGAAGAAGAGGCCUCGGCCAUCCCCAGCACGGCCCAAGAAGUCAGAGGAGUCCAGAUUUUCCCACCUGACCUCUCUGCCUCAGCAGCUGCCUUCCCAGCAGCUGAUGUCCAAGGAUCAGGAUGAGCAAGAGGAACUGGAUUUUCUGUUUGACGAGGAGAUGGAGCAGAUGGAUGGGCGGAAGAACACCUUCACUGCCUGGUCUGAUGAGGAAUCUGACUAUGAGAUUGAUGACAGGGAUGUCAACAAGAUCCUCAUUGUCACCCAGACACCACAUUACAUGCGCCGGCACCCAGGGGGGGACCGCACAGGCAACCACACCUCGCGUGCCAAGAUGAGCGCCGAACUGGCCAAGGUCAUUAAUGAUGGCCUCUUCUACUAUGAGCAGGACCUGUGGGCUGAAAAGUUUGAACCUGAGUAUUCCCAGAUCAAGCAAGAAGUCGAGAACUUCAAAAAGGUCAAUAUGAUCAGCCGGGAGCAGUUUGACACACUGACCCCUGAGCCCCCUGUGGAUCCCAACCAGGAAGUUCCUCCUGGGCCACCUCGGUUCCAGCAAGUUCCUACGGAUGCCCUGGCCAACAAGUUGUUUGGUGCUCCUGAGCCCUCCACCAUCGCCCGCUCUCUACCAACCACUGUCCCAGAGUCACCAAACUACCGCAACACCAGGACCCCUCGCACUCCCCGGACACCACAGCUCAAAGACUCAAGCCAGACAUCACGGUUUUACCCAGUGGUGAAAGAAGGACGGACACUGGAUGCCAAGAUGCCUCGAAAAAGAAAGACAAGACACAGUUCAAACCCACCCUUGGAGAGCCAUGUGGGCUGGGUGAUGGAUUCCCGUGAGCACAGGCCCCGUACUGCUUCCAUCAGCUCCAGCCCCUCAGAAGGGACGCCUACAGUUGGCAGCUAUGGCUGUACCCCUCAGUCAUUGCCCAAGUUCCAGCAUCCUUCCCAUGAACUGCUCAAGGAAAAUGGCUUCACACAACACGUCUACCAUAAGUAUCGUAGGCGCUGCCUUAAUGAGCGGAAACGCUUGGGCAUUGGCCAGUCUCAGGAGAUGAACACACUCUUCCGCUUCUGGUCCUUCUUCCUCCGAGAUCACUUCAACAAAAAGAUGUAUGAGGAGUUCAAGCAGCUGGCUCUGGAGGACGCCAAAGAAGGCUACAGAUAUGGUUUGGAGUGCCUUUUUCGAUACUACAGUUAUGGCCUGGAAAAGAAGUUCCGGCUGGACAUAUUCAAGGAUUUUCAGGAGGAAACGGUGAAGGACUAUGAAGCUGGCCAACUGUAUGGGCUGGAGAAGUUCUGGGCCUUCUUGAAAUAUUCCAAAGCCAAAAAUUUGGACAUUGACCCCAAACUGCAAGAAUACCUCGGCAAAUUCCGACGUCUUGAAGACUUCCGAGUAGAUCCCCCCAUGGGUGAGGAGGGCAACCACAAGCGACACUCAGUGGUAGCAGGAGGUGGCGGCGGUGAGGGCAGGAAGCGGUGCCCCUCCCAGUCUUCCAGCAGGCCUGCUGCCAUGAUCAGCCAACCCCCUACACCACCCACCGGCCAGCCUGUCCGGGAAGAUGCCAAAUGGACAAGCCAGCACUCGAACACACAGACUUUGGGAAAGUGAAAAGCUCCUUAGCCCUGGGGCUUGAGGGGGGAAAGGGGUAGGGUGGGUAAGAGUCCAUGGGGGUGCCCAGUCCCAGGAAAGGGGACAAUGAAGGGACAGGCCUGGAGUUACUAGGACAGGCCUUUGUGCUGAGUAGCAAUGUAUACACCAUUUGGGCUAUCAGAGGUACCCCUGGGCAGGAGCCUCUACAUCCCCUUCCCCCUCCUCUCUCCAUGACUCUUGACAUCCUAGCUUCUUCUAAGGGGGGAGGGAAAGGGGGGAGAUUUUUAUAUAUAUAUACAUAUAUAUAUAUCAAGUUUUAAAUUAUUGAUAGUUCAUCUGGAUUACCAAAAUCACUCUGCAGCCCUGCCCGAGGCUAGUAGGCUGCAACCCUGGUCCCCACCCCUAACCUCCUGCUCCCCCUCAAGCCAACUAUGCAGCCCACAAGAAGGCCCUGCGGGCCCCCCCAUUGCCCAGCACUGUCUCAUAGAAGGCUCUGGUGGUACCUCUGGGCCCCAGGAGCAUCAGCCCCUUGAUCAUCUGGGGUUUGUCAUCACCAUAUUUUCUCCCUGCUGUUCCCACCAUGCCCUUCUGCCAUCUUCUGGGAGAAGGAAACCAAAGGAUCUAAAACUGGGGUUUGGGGGAAGGUUUCAGCCUCUCCCCACUCCCCUUGCCCCACACCCUUUACUCCCCAGCCCAGAGAGACGCUGCUUUUACCAGGAAAGACUAUUGAAAGAUGUUUUAUUUUAUUUUUCUCUGACCUUUCCAUCCUUGAAAAAAUGGGGAAAAAAGAAGAAAAAAGACAAAAUCGACCAUAAAAGACCAAAAAAAAAAAAAAAAUCAGAAAACCCCCACCUAAUCCACAGAAAGUAAUGUCUUUCCCCUCCCCUUGGAAUUUUUGUUUUGUUUUUGGAAAUAAUAUUUUUUUAAAAGUUGCCUUAUUGUGGAGCGGGAAUCUGAAAUACCCAAAUGCCUGUUUUCCUCGGUGGAGUCAACCCGAAGAGCUCCCACCUUCUCUGGAUGUGCCUGGGCUUGGACUGGCUAGAAUCUUUCUCUGGACUGUUGCAUGUACAGUGCCUCCAUCCUGGAGGCAAGAGAGUUGGGAGUGGCUCGAAUCAGAGCCGUGCCCAAGAUAUCCCUGCUGUUGCAUCGUUUGAAGCUGACGUCCUGUGUCUGUACACUGCUGCCACUGUUGUGUCCUCGCUCUGCUUGCUGUUGCCUCACGCCAGGCCCCGUCCUGCCGUGACACCCUUCAUCCUACCCUUGGAACCCCAAGGCCAAGUUGGUUCAAACUGUUGGAGAACAGAGUUGGCCUGCAUCUGGAACACACUUGUCCUCAGCUUACCAUCUCCUCACACCCCAGAGUGGAAAGGUGAACACCUGCAGCUGAGGCUUGGAAACGUUUCUUGUGUUGCCCUGAAAAAUCUUUGAGACCUCAGGGAGGCUCUGUCUCUCUUAAAAGGUGGAGAAAGAUGCCAUUCUCUCCCUAAGGUCUGGUGGAGUCUCCCCAUCUUGCAUACCCUUCUGCAAGCCAUCUAUCUCUGCUCACUCUCCAAUUGACCCGCCUGGGAACAAGGGAUGAGGAGGAGUUGGGGGCUGGGGGGAAUCCUGCCAGUUGGUGAAGCCCUGUGGCAGGAAGGUAUAUGUGGACAUAGAGUAUACCUGAUUCUCUUUCUUCAGCCACUGACUGCUUGGGUUGGGCUGUGAAUGAUAAUGGAAUGGCUGGAGUCUGCUGUUGUCAGAAGGCAGGGAGGGUGAUGAAGGACUGACCCACAUGGACUGGGAUGUGUGUCGGUUAUGGGCAUGACUGCACGUUCACUCUCAGUGGGAUCUGGGCAACAUGGAGUUCAUUGUCCUGUUGCUUACUUACUGCAAUGUCUUUGGCCCUCCUUUUCAACUGGUUCCUCUGUUGGGCCCAAAGGUUGGGAGUAGGAGACAGUAUCCCAGGCUGACAAGGGCUUGCCCUUUACCUUGGGCACCUUGUUAAUUUUUAGCCUGUGCCCUUCCCCACCUUUGCCCUCCCAGUGGUUGGUAUGUGGGAAGCCCAUCUCAGUUCCUGUGACUUCAUGUCUCAAACCAAGGAUGAGCGUCUGGUCUCUGCUAUGAUGGUGGUAUCCGAGGCCUUUCCCUGCCCAGUCUGGUGCCUGCCCCACAUUGUACCGGACACUGGAUUCCUGGACCCCCUUCUCCUUUCCUUUCUUUCCUUCAGGUCACGCAGCCCUGUACUGUAUCCAGCACCACAGAAACCUCAGUGUUUUUCCUCUGCUGGUUUGGGGCACAAGGAAGCCUUAGGGUAUGGGGAAAGGCUGUUAUUACCUAGAGUUUACUCCCAGGCCAGGGGGCUGCCAUCUUCUUCACAGACAUCCCUGAAAGGAAGCCCCUUUGGGGCAGGGAGGUGAGGACUUCAUCUCAACAUCGGCUGGUGGUUGGUAGGGGAGCUUUUUCUUUUCUUUCCUUUUUUUUUGUUUUUGUUUUUGUUUUUGUUUUUGGUAACAUGUUAGGAGUUAAUGUUGCAAAGAGUAGUUUACAUCUUCACUUUCUGAAGACACUUGAAUUUAGGACCGAUGUAUCUGUGACAAGCAUGCCAGAAGUGGCAGGGGCCAUCAGGGCUAACCACUUCACACCUACCAUCGUCCCAUGGGGAUCCAAGACCUGAGAUAAAGCAACAGCCUGCCCAGAUCCCUCUGUUCAUCCUAUCCCUUCCAAGGUUGGUCCAUGCCAACAUAACCUCUGGGCAUCAGACAUCAGCAGGUCUGUGUGCCUCAGCCCUGUUAAGGGGCAGGUUUCUCUUUAGCCCUCUUCCUGCACUUGGGAGCAAAGGCACUACCAGUAGAGAAGGGCCAUCCAGCCGUGCCCCAGCCUGGACCCCUGGGGCUCAGAUAGAGGUGCUGAGCCCCUGUGUCAAAGUUGUUAAAUGUUUUUGUUUUGUUCCAUUGUAGCUCUUUUUUUUUUUUUUUCCCCUUUCCUGGUGAUUGAUUUUACAAAAGAAAGUAAGCUGCUUAGAAGGCCCUGGAAGGGAAGUGAGGAGGAGGGACAAGGAAGAUGACUAGUUACGGAGGGUGAGGGUUGUUUUUUGCCAAAAAGCCUGGGUAGAGUGAUCUGAAUUAUCUGGCACCCUCCUGAAUGGAACCCCAGAGUACCUCCUGUGUGGAAGGGUCCCUGGAUUUUCCCUAACACCCACCCUCUCCCCCUUCAGCCAUGCUGAUGGCAGAGAAGAUAAGAACUUGGAGCCCAUUUCUCACUGGAGAGGAAAACUUGUCAUCUGGCUUUGCGGAGAAGGUUCCACCUUACGCUCGUAGUACAUUAUCUUUACUAUGUGCUAGGAUAUCAUAUUUAAAAGGACAAAAAAAUGUAAAAUACUUGAAUGAGCUUGUAUUAUAACAUUAAUAUUAUUGAGAGUAUCUGCUUUCCAGGCUGAAGUGAUUCAUUCAUUAUUCUAGUCCUGCUUUAGUCCUUUGUAAUUUGUGGUAAUUAUGCUUUUCUUUUUAAUACAAAAAAAUGUAUAAAAAUAAACACUUGAAAAGGCAAAA